AUUCUGGCGCCGCUGACUCCCAGGGCUGGGCUAUCCUCUGAGUCGGGUGAGGCUGGGGCUGGGAGCCGGGCGCCACUGUGGCCGCUGCUUUUCUGAGGGAAAAGAGCGCGGAGUGGGCCAGGUUUUGCAGGCCGGGCCAAGGUGGAGAAAAGGUUCCUGUGGAGCCUCAGGCCGGUGUGCUUUUUUUCCCGGGACUGAGCUUCUGCAGCCCUGAGGCCUGGAGGCCCGGGCGGUAGUAACUGUGCCGGACCAGGUUCGUGGGUGCGGCCUGUGGUGCAGUUGGAGACCGAGGCCCCGCGCAUCCUCGUCCGCGCUUCAGCCACUUAGGCUCGGCCGUAGCGAAAAGGCCCAAGAGGGAAGUCAGAGGUGAACGCCCCAGGAUGAAGGUCCCCUGCAAAACGCUGGGACCUAGAUUUGGGGUGGCGGUUAGUUGGGGCCAGGGAAGCGUGGAGGGUGGGUUCCAAUCGAGUCAAGAAAAGCCUGGGGUGUCCUGAACUCUGCCUGCUUCCCCAGCCCUGCCAGUUUCCAGAGAAGGCGCUUGAGAAGGAGAAACGAAUCGCUGCUGCUCUUCUAAAAGCCGGUUCCCUCUCUGGUGUCUGUGGACCCUGCUUCUGAAGUACAUGAACCUUGAGGAAAAUUGACCAGUUCUAGCAGUUCUAAAAUCAUGGCUCGUGAUUUGGUGAUGUUCAGAGAUGUGGCUGUAGACUUUUCUCAGGAAGAAUGGGAAUGCCUGAACUCAUAUCAGAGGAAUUUGUACAGAGAUGUGAUAUUAGAGAACUAUAGCAACUUGGUGUCACUGGCAGGAUGUUCUAUUUCUAAGCCAGAUGUGAUCACCCUAUUGGAACAAGGGAAAGAGCCCUGGAUGGUUGUGAGGGAUGAGAAAAGAAGAUGGACUCUAGAUUUGGAAUCCAGAUAUGACACUAAAAAGUUAUUUCAAGGAAAGGAUAUUUAUGAAAUGAACUUAUCUCAGUGGAAGGUAAUGGAAAGAAUUAAAAGCUGUGGACUUGAAGAACAAGAAAGUCCUCAUGAGGUGUGUUUCAGGCAAGUGACAAAAACCACCUCUGAAAAAAUGCCUACUUACAGAAAACUCACAUCUCUUCCUCUGUAUCAGAAAAGUCAUAACAGAGAGAAACCCUACGAAUGUGGGGAAUGUGGGAAGGCUUUUAGAGUACGACAACAACUUACUUUCCAUCAAAGAAUUCAUACUGGUGAGAAACCCUAUGAAUGUAAAGAAUGUGGAAAAGCCUUUAGACAGUGUGCCCACCUCAGUCGACAUCAGAGAAUUCAUACUUCUGACAAACUCUAUGAAUGUAAAAAAUGUGGAAAGAUCUUCACAUGUGGCUCAGACCUUCGAGUACAUCAGAGAAUUCAUAUUGGUGAGAAGCCGUAUGAAUGUAAAGAAUGUGGGAAAGCCUUUAGAGUUAGAGGACAACUUAAUCUCCAUCAAAGGAUUCACACGGGUGAGAAACCCUAUGAAUGUAAAGAAUGUGGGAAGGCCUUUAGGCAGUAUGCACACCUUACUCGACAUCAGAGACUGAACAUUGCUGAGAAGUGCUAUGAGUGUAAGGAAUGUGGUCAGGCCUUUCUGUGUAGUACAGGCCUUCGACUACAUCACAAACUUCAUACUGGAGAAAAACCCUAUGAAUGUAAGGAGUGUGGAAAGGCCUUUAGAGUGCGGCAGCAACUUACUCUCCAUCAGAGAAUUCACACUGGUGAGAAGCCUUAUGAUUGUAAGGAAUGUGGGAAGACUUUCAGUCGUGGCUAUCAUCUAACUCUCCAUCAGAGAAUACAUACUGGUGAAAAGCCCUAUGAAUGUAAGGAAUGUCAGAAGUUCUUUCGUCGUUACUCAGAACUUAUUUCACAUCAGGGUAUUCACAUUGGAGAGAAACCUUAUGAAUGUAAGGAAUGUGGGAAGGCAUUUAGGCUGUUCUCACAGCUUACUCAACAUCAGAGUAUUCAUUUUGGUGAGAAACCCUUUAAGUGUAAGGAAUGUGAGAAGACUUUUAGACUGCUUUCACAACUUACCCAACAUCAAAGUAUUCAUACUGGUGAAAAGCCCUAUGACUGUAAGGAAUGUGGAAAGGCCUUUAGACUUCAUUCAUCACUGAUUCAACAUCAGAGAAUUCAUUCUGGUGAGAAACCAUACAAAUGUAAGGAAUGUAAAAAGGCAUUUAGACAACAUUCACAUCUUACUUACCAUCAGCGAAUUCAUAAUGUAACUUAAUAAUUAUUAGAACUCUUCCUUUGCGAAUUUUAUGUUGAGCAUAGGAAGUACAUUCUAGAGGAAAGGUUUUUGAACGUGGGAAUCCCUUUUGCUUCAUGCUCACAACUAAGCAUAGGAAGUUUUAUUUAAAGGAAAGAAUAUGUUAAUGAACAUAUAGAAGCCUUUCAUCACCUUUGAAACCAUGUUAAACUUUAGGAAAUUCAUCCUAGAAAAGAACUUUAUUACAGGACUGAAUGUGGAAAAGCUUUUGAUCUUACCUAUUAUUAUCUCCAUAUUCUUCCAUCUGUGUAUAUACACACGAAGGUUGCUAGGGAACCACUUCAUUCUGAAAAUGUGUAAAUGAAAGGAAAGUCAUUUAGUCUGCAUUUCCUGUAGGAACUGUAUUUCAGGGCAACCAGAAGUUAAGGAGGUAAAGUUCUUCUUUAUUAGAAAAUUCCAGGCUAAUGAAUGCAGAAAGAAUAAUAGAAAAUUAUAUUAGAAAAACUAUUGUGUAACACAUAAUGAAAUAAUGGAUCUAGGCAUGAUUCUCUGUACAGGUUGACACCAUUCAGUGAAGGUUGUGAACUUUAUAGUGAAUAGAUGAGACUGACAACGUCUGAACCCACUCAUCAUCUCAACUUCACAAAAAGCAAGAGAGUAAAAAUUACGUGCCUCCUAAUGUGCUACAGUAAGAUAUACACAUCUUGCCAAAAAUAUUGAACCUGAAUUUAAGCCUCAAGAGCCAACUCCCAGUUUAGAGAAAAUUCAAGGAAUGGAAGAGUAAAUUACAUGACACAAAAAGGAGCAAUUAAAUCUAAAAUAAGGGUAAUUCUACAAGAGGAAUCACCUGGUUUCCCAACCAAUAAAAUGGCAUUUUAAGAAAUAAGGUGGAACUCCUAGGUAUUGACAGACUUGAGACAUCAGUCAAAUGCAAUGAAACAGUGGUUUUUACUUAGAUCAUGAGUUGAACAAACAUGUAAAAGAAGAGAUACUUAACAAUAAUUGGGAGAAUGGAAUAUUGACAAUAUUAGAUAAUAUUAAGAAACUUUGUUAUGUGUGAUAAUAGCAUUGUGGUUAUGUAAAAGUGUAUUUGUUAGAGAUAAUUUCUGAAGUCUAUACACAGGAGAUGAUAUAUCUGGAAUGUCCUUUUGUUCAUACAAAAGAAAAAUGAGGAUGAAUAACAAGUUUGGCAAAAUGAUGGUAACCUAAGUCUUGGAUACAUGGUUUUUAUUUGUUUUGUUUUUGCUAUUCUACUUUUGUGUAUUUAAAAUUUUCCAUGAUGUUCUUUUAAAGAUCAAAUUAUCCAUGAAAUUAUAGCCAGUUUAAAAUGAAUUAUUUUAAAAAAAAUUUCUGGCUGGGCCCGGUGGCUCAUGCCUGUAAUCCCAGCACUUUGGGAGGCCGGUGGGCAGAUCAUGAGGUCAGGAGUUCGAGACCAGCCUGACCAUCAUGGUGAAACCUCAUCUCCACUAAAAAUACAAAAAUUAGCCAGGCGUGGUCACAUGCGCCUGUAAUCCCAGCUACUCGGGCAGCUGAGACAGGAGAAUCACUUGAACCCAGGAGGCAGAGGUUGCAGUGAGCCGAGAUCACGCCAUUGCACUCCAGCCUGGGCAACAAGAGCAAAACUCUAUCUCAAAGAAAAAAAGAAAAUUUCUACAUAUUAAAACUUGUGGAUGUUGCCAAAGCUCUACACAUUGGGAUUGGAAUAUUAAUUACACUAUAAUGACGAUAAUGUAUUCAGGAAGUUAAAAUGUAGGUCCACAUUUUAUUUAGUUGACCUCUCUAUCUCUAUAUUAUAGUACCCAUGGUAUGCACCUUUUUUUUUUUUUUUUUUGAGACGGAGUCUCGCUCUUUCGCCCAGGCUGGCGUGCAGUGGCACAGUCUCGGCUCACUGCAAGCUCUGCCUCCCGGGUUCAAGCCAUUCUCCUCCCUCAGACUUCCGAGUGGCUGGGAUUACAGGCGCCCGCCACCACACCAGGUUGAUUUUUGUAUUUUUAGUAGAGAUGGGGUUUCACCAUGUUGGCCAAGCUGGUCUCAACUCCUGACCUCAGGUGAUCCACCUGCCUUGGCCUCCCAAGGUGCUGGGAUUACAGGCGUGAGCCACCAUGCCCGACUCUCACUUCAUAUGUUUAAAGAAUGAGUAAAAGAAAGCAAUUACUACUGCUAAAUGUGGGAAAUAAUGGACUAGACCUGUACUAAUAUAUGGUAGUCACUAGCAACCUGUUGAGCACUUGAAAUUGAGUUAUUGAGCACUGAAAUGUGGCUAGUCCAAAUUCAAAUGGUGUUUUUUUGUAAAACACAAGAUUCUGAAGACUUAGUUAUUUUAAAAAAGUUAAGUAUCUCAAUUUUUCAUAUUGAGUACAUAUUGAAAUAAUAUUUUAGAUAUAUUGGUUCAAAUAAAAUACAUUAAAAUGAAUAACACUUUUUUGUUUUUAAAAUUGUUAUAGGAAAAUUUAUAUAUGUAGCUCACGUAUUUCUAUUGUCAGCGCUGGCAUAAACAAUAAAAAGUAGACUUGGUUUUUUUGUGUGUGUUUCUUUAAAAGAUACCAAUAUAGUCAAGACCUUUGCAGUUUUGAUCACAGAAAUAUGAAAGAUUACACAGCUACAGCUAUAUGAAUGAUAAAAGUGACAGCUAUGGAUUUUUAAAGUUAUAAGUUGCUAUACUACAUAUAUGUAAUGUGUGUGUGUAUAGUGUGUAGGUAUAUAUAUUUAUAUUUAUACACACACUAUACAUGUAUUUUAAAAUAUUGAAAAUCCAGAAUUAUUUUAUGGUAAAAAUUACUAAAAUUGACUUCACAUGCUGAAUGAAGAGAGCCUGAGUAGACCAACAAACAAAUGAAAAAUUAAGACGGUUAGAAGAUACGCUUUCUAAAAGAAUACAUUUAGAAUCUAACUUUAAAAAAAAAAAAUCCUACUCUCCUGAGCCAGAGUGGUCUCAGAGAGACUCCGAGAACCUAAUUUUUUACAAGUAAAAUCUUUGAAGAAUUGGUAAUUGCUAAAUUUUUCCAACAUACUAUUCUACAAGACUAACCUAAAACUGAUUAUAAGAACUAGGUGAGGAGGGCUGGCAAAACGAAAAUCUAGACAUUUUCCGUAUGAAGAGAAAUCUGGUAAUUCUAAUUUCUAUGGGAAAUUAUAUCCAACAGUUUAGAAUAGAAAAUCAUUUAUGUGGAAUAACUUGGACCAGAUCCAUCCAGCUUUAAUUAUAUAUUUAGAUUCUAGGCAUUCUACCUUCAGAACAUCAUAAUGAUAGUAAAAGAGAUACGAUUCUGGCCCAGUAUCAUCUCAAUUCAUGCUUAUUGUCUUUUUUUUUUUUUUUUUUUUAGCUUUCUAUGUAUUAAGAAUGGAAUGAAUUUUAUGUAUGUAAAAGUGUAACCCAACACCUUAAAAUUACCUUCUCAAAAUUAAUAAAGACAGAGUUCUUAUAAAUGAUUGCAUCAGUUGGACUUCGGUGAUUUCACCGUGGUCAUCCAUUAUGAACUGUAUUUGCUGUUAUAAUUGGGAAGCCAUGAUGUUCAGUGUAUUACAUCAUUAUAUUCCAUUUCUCAAAUGGAAUAUGAAACUUGAUAGCAUUUGAAACCAUUUCCCAGGAAACACUAGUGCUUGAUGGUAUUUUUAGAAAGCAUUCUGUGGUUAAAUGAGCAUAUUAAAAUUAAUAAUUAAGAAAAUAAAACUAUAGCUUCUCCAAAUAAUGAAGUAAUGAGAGUUUAAUUGAUUUUAUUUAACUUAAUGUAUCUGAAGCACCUUUUACCCUGUAACUUUCACUCUUAAUGCUUGUGAGUAUGGGAUAUGAACCCAUUUUAACAGAUAAGUGCUGUAACCAAAACAGGUGACAGCAAAGGUGGAAAGUUCGGACCUCAUGUCAGGUGGUUAGUUGUGUUGGAAGGUGGAUGUGAGGUAUGUUUCCCUGGAUGUGGCAUCAUGUUCUAAAGUCACCUGUUCUUUCUGAAUAUUGAACUGUUGCUUUUCUGCAGAAAUAAAAUUUCUGAAUCAACACUA